GCGCACCCACCUGCUGCAUCUUAGUUCAGUCGGCUCUUAGAGUAGUAACCGCCAGAAAGGAGUCGGAAGAGGUCUCACGAGGCUGUCAUCACCGCCAUGCCCAAGAAUAAAGGUAAAGGAGGUAAAAACAGGCGCAGGGGUAAAAAUGAGAAUGAAUCUGAAAAAAGAGAGUUGGUGUUUAAAGAGGAUGGACAAGAGUAUGCUCAGGUAAUCAAAAUGUUGGGAAAUGGACGAUUGGAAGCAUUGUGUUUUGAUGGUGUAAAGAGGUUAUGCCAUAUCAGAGGGAAAUUGAGAAAAAAGGUUUGGAUAAAUACAUCAGACAUUAUAUUGGUUGGUCUACGGGACUAUCAGGAUAACAAAGCUGAUGUAAUUUUAAAGUACAAUGCAGAUGAAGCUAGAAGCCUGAAGGCAUAUGGCGAGCUUCCAGAACAUGCUAAAAUCAAUGAAACAGACACAUUUGGUCCUGGAGAUGAUGAUGAAAUCCAGUUUGACGAUAUUGGAGAUGAUGAUGAAGACAUUGAUGAUAUCUAAAUUGAACCAAGUGUUUUUACAUGACAAGUUCUCUGAGGAUGGUUCUACAGUUGGGAUUUUGGCCAUCAUCAACCAAGAAGAGAAAUUCAUUUAGUGUGUAGUUUCUGAAAGCAAACUGAUUUAUUUUCAUUGUUUUAAAGUAUUUAUUUCUUUAAAAGCUGAGGACACUGAAUUACCUUAAGUUAAAUGUUAAUACUUUAUUGUUUUGAUGUAAUGGAACUUAAGGAUAAAAGACCAUAAUAUUUGCUGUUAAAAUAAAUAAACGAGUGCCUUUCCUACUGUGAUAACGUCAAGUAAUUGGAUAUUUUGAAUACAUUUCUGCCUGAUAAUCAUGCUGGGUUCUAAUAAGCCCUACUUCCACCUAAUCUGUUUACAGUCUUUUGGUAUGUUUCAGUUACUUAGAUGGUCUCAUAAGGUUUCUGAUACAAUUUGAAGACAGAAAUCUGCAUUUAGAAUCAGAAAACAUGGACAUAUUUUUCAUAUUUAUCUAGUCAUAUGUAAUUUUAUGCUAACAUUGAUAGUUUAUAAAUCCUUUUCAUCCUUUGUGCCUCGGUUAUUAAGGAAAAAAAAAUGUCCAACAUACAGUUUUUAAAGUGUGGCAGUUUUGAGUAGUAACUUAGAAUGUAUAAGAUUAAGAGUUAAAGAAACCGAACAAUAAGUGGCAACCAAUUAUCUUAACAUUGGAAAUACUGGGGUGCCAUUUUGUUUUCAAAAGUUAUUCAUUGUAAUCCACUGUUUUGGCUUUCAUGAACAAGUAAAUUACAGUGUAUAAAUGAAAAGCAAUUUCAUAAUAAAUUCUAUAAACUGA